CUGAGCGCCGCGGGCCUGCGCCAUUGAGGAGCGGCGGGGAGGAAACGCCGCGCAGCGCCGGGCUGGGGCGGGCGGCCCGGGACACCGACAGAUUUUUCUGUGACCAUGAAAGAGAGAAAUAAAGAAUGAUCCAUGAUUUCUAAACACCUUUUCCUGAGGAUAUAGUCAUGUUGGAAGGCCUUGUAGCCUGGGUUCUCAAUACCUAUUUGGGAAAAUAUGUCAAUAACCUGAACACUGACCAGCUCUCAGUUGCACUUCUCAAAGGUGCUGUUGAAUUAGAAAACUUGCCAUUAAAGAAAGAUGCCUUGAAAGAAUUGGAAUUACCAUUUGAAGUCAAAGCUGGCUUCAUUGGGAAAGUAACCCUUCAGAUUCCCUUUUAUCGCCCCCAUGUGGACCCUUGGGUGAUCUCCAUCUCCAGCCUUCACUUAAUUGGAGCCCCAGAGAAAAUACAGGAUUUCAAUGAUGAAAAGGAGAAGCUGUUGGAAAGGGAACGUAAGAAAGCACUACUUCAAGCCCUGGAGGAGAAAUGGAAGAAUGACCGCCAGCAGAAAGGGGAGUCCUAUUGGUAUUCAGUUACCGCCUCCGUAGUUACAAGGAUUGUGGAGAAUAUUGAAUUAAAAAUUCAAGAUGUCCAUUUACGCUUUGAAGAUGGUGUCACCAAUCCCUCCCAUCCUUUUGCUUUUGGCAUCUGCAUUAAGAAUGUGUCCAUGCAAAAUGCUGUGAAUGAGCCUGUACAGAAACUAAUGCGGAAAAAGCAAUUAGACGUAGCAGAAUUUAGCAUCUAUUGGGAUGUCGAUUGCACUUUACUGGGGGAUUUGCCUCAGAUGGAGUUACAGGAGGCCAUGGCCAGGAGCAUGGAGAGUCGCAGCCAUCACUACGUCCUGGAGCCUGUGUUUGCAUCUGCUCUUUUGAAGAGAAACUGCUCCAAGAAGCCCCUGCGGUCUCGGCACAGUCCCCGUAUUGAUUGUGAUAUUCAGCUGGAGACCAUUCCCUUGAAACUCUCUCAGCUGCAAUACCGGCAAAUCAUGGAAUUCCUCAAGGAGCUGGAACGAAAGGAGAGGCAGGUGAAGUUCCGAAGGUGGAAACCCAAGGUGGCGAUAUCUAAGAACUGCCGAGAAUGGUGGUAUUUUGCUUUGAAUGCUAACUUGUAUGAGAUCAGAGAGCAGAGGAAACGUUGCACCUGGGACUUUAUGUUGCACCGCGCUCGUGAUGCUGUAUCUUACACUGACAAAUAUUUCAACAAGUUAAAAGGAGGCCUGCUGUCCACAGAUGACAAGGAGGAAAUGUGUCGGAUUGAAGAGGAACAGAGCUUUGAGGAAUUGAAGAUUUUGCGUGAACUGGUUCAUGAUCGAUUUCACAAACAGGAAGAACUAGCAGAGAGUCUGCGGGAGCCUCAGUUUGAUUCUCCAGGAGCCUGUCCGGGAGCCCCAGAACCCGGUGGAGGCAGUGGGAUGCUGCAGUAUCUCCAGUCCUGGUUUCCUGGAUGGGGUGGCUGGUACGGGCAGCAGACCCCAGAAGGGAAUGUGGUUGAGGGACUGUCAGCAGAGCAACAGGAGCAGUGGAUUCCUGAAGAGAUCCUGGGCACUGAGGAGUUUUUUGACCCCACUGCAGAUGCCUCGUGUAUGAACACGUAUACAAAGCGAGAUCAUGUCUUUGCCAAACUGAAUUUGCAGUUGCAGCGAGGUACAGUGACUCUGUUACACAAGGAGCAAGGAACUCCUCAAAUGAAUGAAAGUGCUUUCAUGCAGCUCGAGUUUUCAGAUGUAAAACUUCUAGCAGAGUCUCUUCCUCGAAGAAAUUCCUCGUUGCUUUCAGUCCGGUUGGGUGGACUGUUUCUUCGAGACCUGGCUACAGAAGGAACUAUGUUUCCUCUUCUAGUCUUCCCUAAUCCACAAAAAGAAGUUGGCAGAGUCUCACAAUCUUUUGGUCUACAAACUACAUCUGCAGACAGAAGUGAUCAUUACCCAGCUGCAGAUCCAGAUGGCCCCGUUUUUGAGAUGCUGUAUGAGAGAAAUCCGGCGCACAGCCACUUUGAGAGGCGGCUCAAUGUCAGCACAAGGCCCUUGAACAUCAUAUACAAUCCGCAGGCCAUUAAAAAAGUAGCAGACUUUUUCUACAAGGGAAAGGUUCAUACCUCAGGUUUUGGUUAUCAGUCUGAACUUGAGCUGAGAGUGGCUGAAGCUGCCCGAAGACAAUAUAACAAGCUGAAGAUGCAGACCAAGGCAGAAAUCCGGCAAACUCUUGAUCGUUUGCUAGUGGGUGAUUUCAUUGAGGAGAGUAAACGAUGGACCGUGCGGCUGGAUAUUUCUGCCCCUCAGGUGAUAUUUCCUGAUGAUUUCAAAUUCAAGAAUCCUGUGUUAGUUGUCGUGGAUCUAGGAAGAAUGCUUUUGACGAACACCCAAGAUAACUCCAGGAGGAAAAGUAGGGAUGGGUCAGCAUCUGAAGAGACCCAGUUUAGUGAUGAUGAAUAUAAGACCCCCCUGGCCACACCUCCUAACACCCCACCUCCCGAGUCAAGCAGCAGCAACGGAGAGAAAACACCUCCCUUUUCUGGAGUUGAGUUCAGUGAAGAACAGCUUCAAGCACAUUUAAUGAGCACAAAGAUGUAUGAGAGGUACUCGCUGUCAUUUAUGGACCUCCAGAUCAUGGUUGGACGAGUGAAAGACAAUUGGAAGCAUGUCCAGGAUAUUGACGUGGGACCAACACAUGUGGUAGAGAAGUUCAACGUUCACCUACAGUUAGAGCGUCGAUUGAUUUAUACUUCAGAUCCCAAAUAUCCAGGAGCCGUGCUCUCAGGCAACUUACCAGACUUAAAAAUCCACAUUAAUGAAGAUAAAAUAUCUGCACUAAAGAAUUGCUUUGCUCUCCUCACCACCCCAGAAAUGAAAACUUCUGACACUCAGAUUAAAGAAAAGAUUUUUCCCCAGGAGGAGCAGCGGGGAAGUUUGCAAGACUCCGUAAUGAAUUUAACCCAGAGCAUUGUGUUGUUGGAGCAGCAUACCCGCGAGGUUCUGGUGGAGUCGCAGCUCCUCCUGGCGGAAUUUAAAGUGAACUGUAUGCAGCUUGGUGUUGAGAGCAAUGGCCGGUACAUUUCUGUGCUCAAGGUGUUUGGUACCAAUGCUCACUUUGUGAAGAGGCCUUAUGAUGCUGAAGUCUCCCUAACUGUUCAUGGUUUGCUCCUGGUGGAUACCAUGCAGACAUAUGGUGCUGAUUUUGACCUUUUGAUGGCUUCACAUAAGAACUUGAGCUUUGAUAUUCCAACGGGAAGCCUUCGGGAUAGCAGGGCCCAGUCUCCUGUCUCUGGACCGAAUGUGGCCCACUUAACUGAUGGAGCUACACUGAACGACCGAUCAGCUACUAGUGUUUCACUUGACAAAAUUCUUACCAAAGAGCAAGAGUCCCUUAUUAAGUUGGAAUAUCAGUUUGUGAGUUCAGAGUGCCCAUCGAUGAAUUUAGACAGUACUCUUCAGGUGAUUUCCCUACAGGUGAAUAAUUUAGAUAUUAUCCUCAAUCCAGAGACGAUUGUGGAGCUAAUUGGUUUUCUUCAAAAAUCCUUUCCCAAGGAAAAAGAUGAUUUAAGUCCUCAACCUUUAAUGACUGAUUUUGAAAGAAGCUUCAGAGAACAAGGAACUUACCAGUCUACAUAUGAACAAAACACUGAGGUUGCAGUGGAAAUCCAUAGGCUGAACUUACUGCUUCUUCGGACAGUGGGCAUGGCAAAUAGAGAGAAAUAUGGCAGAAAAAUUGCAACUGCAAGUAUAGGUGGCACCAAAGUUAAUGUCUCAAUGGGUAGCACGUUUGACAUGAAUGGUUCUCUUGGCUGUUUACAGCUUAUGGAUUUGACACAAGAUAACGUUAAAAACCAGUAUGUUGUCAGCAUUGGGAAUUCUGUAGGCUAUGAAAAUAUCAUCAGUGAUAUUGGCUACUUUGAAUCUGUGUUUGUCAGAAUGGAAGAUGCAGCCCUCACUGAAGCUUUGAGUUUCACGUUUGUUGAGAGAUCUAAACAGGAGUGUUUUCUCAACCUGAAGAUGGCUUCUUUACAUUAUAACCACUCUGCUAAGUUUUUGAAGGAGUUGACGUUAUCCAUGGAUGAACUGGAAGAAAAUUUUCGAGGUAUGCUGAAAAGCGCAGCCACCAAAGUCACCACAGUACUAGCUACCAAGACUGCCGAGUAUAGCGAGAUGGUAUCGCUCUUUGAAACUCCAAGGAAGACUCGGGAACCCUUUAUCUUAGAGGAAAAUGAAAUAUAUGGGUUUGACCUAGCUUCGUCUCAUUUGGACACUGUAAAGCUAAUCUUGAACAUAAACAUUGAAUCACCAGUUGUUUCUAUCCCUCGGAAGCCGGGGAGUCCUGAGUUGUUGGUGGGACACUUGGGACAGAUAUUCAUCCAGAAUUUUGUGGCGGGAGAUGAUGAAUCCAGAAGUGACCGUCUGCAGGUGGAAAUCAAGGACAUUAAACUGUAUUCUUUGAAUUGCACCCAGUUGGCAGGUAGAGAAGCUGUUGGGUCUGAAGGAAGCCGGAUGUUUUGCCCACCUUCCGGGUCUGGCAGUGCCAACAGUCAGGAGGAAGCUCAUUUCACACGACAUGAUUUCUUUGAAUCUUUGCAUAGAGGUCAAGCUUUUCACAUCCUGAACAACACCACCAUUCAGUUUAAACUGGAGAAGAUCCCUAUAGAGAGAGAAUCUGAAUUGACUUUUUCUCUUAGCCCAGAUGACCUGGGAACUUCUAGCAUCAUGAAGAUUGAAGGAAAAUUUGUCAAUCCAGUUCAGGUGGUGUUAGCAAAGCAUGUAUAUGAGCAGGUUUUACAAACCCUGGACAAUCUCGUGUACAGUGAAGAUCUGAAUAAGUAUCCAGCCAGUGCUACCUCCUCCCCUUGCCCUGAUUCUCCUCUGCCUCCCCUCAGUACCUGUGGAGAAUCUUCUGUUGAAAGGAAGGAGAAUGGAUUGUUCAGCCACUCCAGCCUUUCUAACACCUCUCAGAAGUCAUUGUCAGUGAAGGAAGUCAAAUCCUUUACUCAGAUUCAAGCCACCUUUUGUAUAUCAGAGCUUCAGGUUCAGCUAAGUGGAGAUCUGACUUUGGGGGCCCAAGGUCUUGUGAGCUUAAAGUUUCAGGACUUUGAGGUGGAAUUCAGUAAAGACCAUCCCCAGACUUUAUCUAUUCAGAUUGCCCUGCAUUCUCUGCUGAUGGAGGACUUAUUGGAGAAGAAUCCAGAUUCUAAAUAUAAGAACCUGAUGGUGUCUCGAGGAGCCCCUAAGCCAUCUAGUUUAGCACAAAAAGAAUACCUUUCUCAGUCUUGCCCCUCAGUGUCCAAUGUGGAAUAUCCUGAUAUGCCUCGGUCUCUCCCUUCCCACAUGGAAGAAGCUCCUAAUGUCUUCCAGUUGUAUCAAAGGCCCACCUCUGCGUCCCGGAAAAAGCAAAAGGAAGUCCAAGACAAGGACUAUCCCUUGACCCCACCUCCUUCUCCAACAGUGGAUGAGCCCAAGAUACUUGUUGGAAAGAGUAAAUUUGAUGAUUCCUUAGUCCACAUCAACAUAUUCUUGGUAGAUAAGAAACAUCCAGAAUUCUCUUCCAGUUACAAUCGAGUUAACCGGAGCAUUGAUGUUGAUUUUAAUUGCUUGGAUGUGCUGAUCACACUGCAAACCUGGGUUGUGAUAUUAGACUUUUUUGGAAUCGGCUCCACUGCAGACAACCACGCAAUGAGGCUGCCUCCUGAGGGCAUUCUGCACAACGUGAAGUUGGAGCCACAUGCCUCCAUGGAGUCUGGACUUCAGGAUCCAGUGAACACCAAACUGGAUCUCAAGGUUCAUUCACUUUCUCUAGUGCUGAAUAAGACCACCAGUGAGCUUGCCAAAGCAAAUGUGUCCAAAUUAGUAGCACACCUGGAAAUGAUUGAGGGAGACCUGGCCUUACAGGGCAGCAUUGGGAGUCUGUCUCUAAGUGACCUCACAUGCCAUGGAGAGUUCUACAGAGAACGGUUCACUACCAGUGGUGAAGAAGCACUCAUCUUCCAGACUUUUAAAUACGGACGGCCUGACCCUCUGCUCCGGAGAGAACACGACAUUCGCGUGAGCCUCCGGAUGGCCUCUGUGCAGUAUGUGCAUACUCAGCGUUUCCAGGCAGAGGUGGUGGCCUUCAUUCAGCAUUUCACUCAGCUGCAGGAUGUCUUAGGGCGCCAGCGAGCUGCUAUUGAGGGGCAGACGGUGAGAGAUCAAGCCCAGCGCUGUUCACGGGUUCUCCUGGAUAUUGAGGCUGGUGCUCCCGUUCUCUUGAUCCCAGAAAGUUCCAGAUCAAAUAAUCUGAUUGUAGCAAAUUUGGGGAAGUUGAAAGUCAAAAAUAAGUUUCUGUUUGCUGGUUUUCCUGGCACCUUUUCCCUACAAGAUAAGGAAUCUGUGCCUUCAGCUUCCCCAACGGGUAUUCCCAAACACAGUCUGAGGAAAACGACAAGCACGGAGGAGCCCAGGGGAACCCAUUCCCAGGGGCAGUUCACGAUGCCUCUUGCUGGAAUGAGCCUAGGAAGCCUGAAGAGUGAGUUUGUGCCCAGUACCUCCACCAAGCAGCAAGGGCCGCAACCCACACUGUCUGUUGGCCAAGAGUCCAGUAGUCCAGAAGACCAUGUCUGCCUGCUGGAUUGCGUUGUCGUGGAUCUCCAGGACAUGGACAUCUUUGCUGCAGAGAGACAUCCGAGAGAAUACUCGAAGGCACCAGAGGAUAGUAGUGGAGAUCUGAUCUUCCCUUCCUAUUUUGUGCGACAGACAGGAGGAAGCCUCUUAACCGAGCCUUGUAGGCUGAAAUUGCAGGUGGAAAGGAAUUUGGACAAAGAAAUAAGUCAUACUGUGCCAGACAUAUCUAUCCAUGGCAAUCUCUCCUCAGUCCACUGCUCUCUGGAUCUGUAUAAAUACAAGCUGAUCCGCGGCUUAUUAGAGAACAACCUGGGAGAACCCAUAGAGGAAUUUAUGCGGCCUUAUGAUUUACAAGAUCCAAGAAUUCAUACUGUCCUGAGUGGAGAAGUGUACACCUGUAUGUGCUUCCUCAUUGAUAUGGUGAAUGUAAGUCUGGAGCUUAAAGAUCCAAAAAGAAAAGAAGGUGCUGGGUCCCUAGCCAGAUUUGACUUCAAGAAAUGCAAACUGCUCUAUGAAAGUUUUUCCAACCAAACCAAGUCCAUUAACUUGGUUUCCCAUUCCAUGAUGGCUUUUGACACCCGUUAUGCUGGGCAGAAGACCAGCCCUGGCAUGACGAAUGUGUUCAGCUGUAUCUUUCAGCCCGCUAAGAACAGCAGCACCACCCAAGGGUCCAUUCAGAUUGAACUACAUUUCAGAUCUACCAAGGAUUCCUCCUGCUUUACAGUAGUUCUCAACAAUCUCCGUGUGUUUCUCAUAUUUGACUGGCUACUGUUAGUCCAUGAUUUUCUCCACACUCCCAGUGAUAUUAAGAAACAAAAUCAUGUUACUCCUUCUCGCCACCGUAACUCUAGCAGCGAAUCUGCUAUAGUUCCCAAAACUGUGAAGAGUGGAGUAGUUACCAAGCGGUCUUCCCUUCCUGUGUCCAAUGAAAGGCACCUGGAGGUCAAGGUCAAUGUAACAGGUACGGAGUUUGUGGUCAUUGAAGAUGUGUCCUGCUUCGACACCAAUGCCAUUAUUCUGAAAGGCACCACAGUGCUCACCUAUAAGCCCCGGUUUGUUGAUCGCCCCUUUUCAGGAAGUUUGUUUGGCAUUGAGGUGUUUUCAUGCCGACUAGGGAAUGAGCAUGAUACAGCUCUUUCAAUUGUGGAUCCCGUACAAAUUCAAAUGGAGUUGGUGGGGAAUUCUUCUUAUCAAAAUAGUUCAGGAUUGAUGGAUGCAUUCAAUAGUGAAGAUUUCCCACCUGUCCUGGAGAUUCAGUUACAAGCCCUGGAUAUCAGACUCUCCUAUAAUGAUGUUCAGCUGUUUCUUGCCAUUGCAAAAUCCAUCCCAGAGCAAGCUAAUGCUGCAGUGCCAGACUCAGUGGCCCUGGAGUCAGACUCCGUUGGCACUUACCUUCCAGGUGCAUCUCGCGUUGGAGAGGAAAUCAGAGAAGGGACAAGACACACCUUAGAUCCUGUCUUGGAGUUACAGCUGGCUAGGCUGCAGGAGCUGGGAUUCAGCAUGGAUGAUUGUCGCAAAGCUCUUUUGGCGUGUCAAGGCCAAUUGAAAAAGGCAGCAAGUUGGUUGUUUAAGAAUGCGGAACCUCUGAAGUCUCUUUCCUUGGCCUCCACCAGCCGAGAUAGCCCAGGGGCUGUGGCAGCGCCAUUGAUCUCUGGCGUGGAGAUCAAAGCUGAGAGUGUGUGCAUCUGUUUCAUCGAUGACUGCAUGGAUUGUGAUGUUCCUCUCGCUGAACUCACCUUUUCCCGUCUGAAUUUUCUUCAGCGUGUAAGAACUAGCCCUGAAGGCUAUGCCCACUUCACCCUUUCUGGAGAUUAUUAUAACCGUGCUCUUUCAGGCUGGGAGCCAUUUAUUGAGCCUUGGCCAUGCUCUGUAUCCUGGCAACAGCAGGCAGCUAGUCGUCUCCAUCCUCCUCGACUGAAGCUAGAAGCCAAGGCCAAACCUCGUUUGGAUAUCAAUAUCACUUCUGUGCUAAUUGACCAGUAUGUAAGUACCAAGGAAUCGUGGAUGGCAGAUUACUGUAAAGAUGACAAGGACAUAGAGUCAGCUAAAUCAGAAGACUGGAUGGGCUCUUCGGUGGAUCCUCCAUGUUUUGGACAAAGCCUCCCCCUUGUCUACCUUAGAACUAGGAGUACAGCCAGUCUGACUAACCUAGAGCACCAGAUCUAUGCUAGAGCAGAGGUGAAAACCCCCAAGCGCCGGCAGCCAUUUGUCCCCUUUGCUCUGAGGAACCACACGGGGUGCACUUUGUGGUUUGCCACCCUGACCACCACACCCACCAGAGCUGCACUCUCUCACAGUGGGAGUCCAGGGGUAGUUCCAGAAGGGAACGGAACAUUUCUCGAUGAUACUCACAAUGUUAGUGAAUGGCGAGAAGUCCUUACAGGUGAAGAGAUUCCCUUUGAAUUUGAAGCAAGAGGAAAGUUAAGACACAGACACACCCAUGACCUCCGGAUUCAUCAACUGCAAGUGAGAGUAAAUGGCUGGGAGCAAGUGAGCCCAGUGUCUGUGGACAAAGUCGGGACCUUUUUUCGAUAUGCAGCACCAGAUAAAAAUUCAUCUUCCUCUACGAUUGGCAGCCCAAGCAGCAGAACAAAUAUUAUACAUCCCCAGGUUUAUUUCUCUUCACUCCCACCAGUGCGGGUGGUCUUUGCAGUGACUAUGGAAGGCAGUGCACGGAAAGUCAUCACUGUCCGGUCAGCCCUCAUUGUGAGGAACAGACUUGAGACACCAAUGGAACUAAGACUGGAUAGCCCAUCAGCUCCAGACAAGCCAGUGGUGCUUCCUGCUAUCAUGCCAGGGGAUUCGUUUGCUGUGCCUUUACACCUCACUUCUUGGCGGCUACAGGCCCGGCCCAAAGGAUUGGGUGUAUUUUUCUGUAAGGCUCCCAUUCAUUGGACCAAUGUAGUGAAGACUGCAGAAAUUAGUAGCAGUAAACGAGAGUGCCACUCUAUGGACACAGAAAAAAGCCGAUUUUUCAGGUUUUGUGUGGCUAUAAAGAAAGAGAAUUAUCCAGAUUAUAUGCCCUCAAACAUAUUUUCUGACAGUGCAAAACAGAUUUUCAGACAGCCUGGGCAUACCAUAUAUCUCCUGCCAACUGUGGUAAUCUGCAACUUGCUACCCUGUGAACUUGAUUUUUAUGUUAAAGGAAUGCCAAUUAAUGGGACGCUGAAACCUGGCAAGGAGGCAGCUCUCCAUACAGCUGAUACAUCCCAGAACAUUGAGCUGGGGGUAUCACUGGAGAAUUUCCCCCUCUGUAAAGAAUUGCUCAUUCCACCUGGAACCCAAAACUAUAUGGUGAGAAUGCGACUCUAUGACGUCAACCGUCGGCAGCUGAACCUCACCAUCCGGAUUGUGUGUCGAGCAGAAGGAUCCUUAAAGAUCUUCAUUUCUGCUCCAUAUUGGCUGAUUAACAAAACAGGGUUGCCACUGAUCUUCAGACAGGACAAUGCCAAGACAGAUGCUGCAGGCCAGUUUGAGGAGCAUGAGCUGGCCCGUAGCCUGAGUCCUCUCUUAUUCUGCUAUGCUGACAAAGAGCAGCCAAACCUCUGCACGAUGAGAAUCGGAAGGGGGAUUCAUCCAGAAGGCAUGCCGGGCUGGUGUCAGGGCUUCUCCCUGGAUGGUGGUAGUGGUGUCCGAGCUUUGAAAGUCAUCCAGCAAGGAAACCGCCCAGGGCUGAUCUAUAACAUUGGUAUUGAUGUCAAGAAAGGCCGAGGUCGAUACAUUGAUACCUGCAUGGUCAUCUUUGCCCCCCGUUACCUGUUAGAUAAUAAAUCAUCUCACAAGCUUGCAUUUGCACAGAGGGAAUUUGCCAGGGGACAGGGAACAGCCAAUCCCGAAGGUUACAUUUCCACCCUUCCUGGUUCCAGUGUGGUGUUCCACUGGCCUCGGAAUGACUAUGAUCAGCUAUUGUGUGUCAGACUGAUGGACGUUCCCAAUUGUAUUUGGUCUGGAGGCUUUGAAGUCAACAAGAAUAAUUCCUUCCAUAUCAACAUGAGGGAUACCUUGGGAAAAUGCUUCUUCCUACGAGUGGAAAUUACUCUCCGAGGAGCUACGUAUAGGAUCUCAUUUAGUGACACAGAUCAGUUACCUCCUCCUUUCCGAAUUGACAACUUUUCUAAGGUCCCGGUUGUCUUUACUCAGCAUGGCGUAGCUGAACCCAGGCUCCGGACUGAAGUGAAGCCCAUGACUUCAUUGGAUUAUGCCUGGGACGAACCCACCUUGCCACCUUUUAUCACUCUGACUGUUAAAGGGGCAGGGUCCUCUGAGAUCAACUGCAACAUGAAUGAUUUCCAGGAUAAUCGGCAGCUUUAUUAUGAAAAUUUCAUUUACAUUGCUGCUACAUAUACAUUCUCUGGCUUGCAGGAGGGAACAGGCAGGCCUGUGGCUUCCAACAAGGCCAUUACCUGUGCGGAGCUCGUUUUGGAUGUCUCACCCAAGACACAAAGAGUCAUUUUAAAAAAGAAGGAACCAGGAAAGCGUUCUCAGCUGUGGAGGAUGACAGGAACAGGAAUGCUGGCCCAUGAGGGCUCCUCAGUUCCUCACAAUCCCAAUAAGCCCUCAGCCGCCCGCUCCACCGAGGGGUCUGCCAUCUUAGAUAUUGCUGGUCUCGCUGCAGUGACUGACAACAGAUACGAGCCACUGAUGCUGAGAAAGCCUGACCGCAGGCGAAGCACAACUCAGACGUGGAGUUUCCGAGAAGGAAAACUGACCUGUGGGUUACAUGGGUUGGUCGUCCAGGCCAAAGGAGGACUUUCUGGUUUGUUUGAUGGAGCUGAAGUUGUUCUUGGUCCUGACACUUCCAUGGAGCUUUUGGGGCCAGUUCCACCUGAACAACAAUUUAUUAAUCAAAAAAUGAGACCUGGUUCUGGAAUGUUAUCCAUCAGAGUCAUCCCAGAUGGACCAACUAGAGCACUCCAGAUAACAGAUUUCUGCCACCGGAAAAGCAGCCGUUCAUAUGAAGUGGAUGAACUUCCUGUCACCGAACAAGAGCUGCAGAAAUUAAAGAAUCCAGAUACAGAGCAGGAAUUGGAAGUGCUUGUGAGGUUAGAAGGUGGAAUUGGGUUGUCCUUAAUUAAUAAAGUCCCAGAAGAACUGGUCUUUGCAAGUCUUACAGGAAUCAAUGUGCACUAUACACAGCUGGCAACCAGUCACAUGCUUGAACUCAGCAUACAGGAUGUACAGGUGGACAAUCAGCUCAUUGGUACCACGCAGCCCUUCAUGCUCUAUGUGACUCCCCUGAGCAAUGAGAAUGAGGUCAUCGAGACCGGCCCAGCUGUGCAAGUCAACGCAGUGAAGUUCCCCAGUAAGAGUGCACUGACCAACAUCUACAAGCAUCUGAUGAUCACAGCUCAGAGAUUCACAGUGCAAAUUGAGGAGAAACUGCUCCUCAAGCUGCUAAGUUUCUUUGGCUACGAUCAAGCAGAAUCAGAGGUGGAAAAAUAUGAUGAAAACCUCCAUGAAAAGACAGCUGAGCAAGGUGGAACACCAAUUCGAUACUACUUUGAAAAUCUCAAAAUCAGCAUUCCUCAGAUCAAGCUAAGUGUGUUCACCUCCAACAAGCUCCCAUUGGAUCUUAAGGCCCUAAAAAGCACCUUGGGGUUUCCUUUGAUACGGUUUGAAGACGCUGUGAUUAAUCUAGAUCCAUUCACUCGGGUACAUCCCUAUGAGACCAAGGAGUUCAUCAUCAAUGAUAUCCUCAAACAUUUCCAGGAGGAACUCCUCAGCCAGGCAGCUCGAAUCCUGGGAUCAGUGGAUUUUCUUGGCAAUCCUAUGGGGCUUUUGAAUGAUGUUUCUGAAGGGGUUACUGGACUGAUAAAAUAUGGAAAUGUCGGGGGCCUCAUCAGAAAUGUUACACACGGAGUAUCAAACUCUGCUGCCAAGUUUGCUGGAACAUUAUCAGAUGGCUUAGGGAAGACGAUGGACAAUCGGCAUCAGUCAGAGCGGGAGUACAUCAGGUACCAUGCAGCCACAAGUGGUGAACACCUUGUAGCCGGCAUCCAUGGCCUGGCUCAUGGUAUCAUUGGUGGACUGACCAGUGUUAUAACUUCGACAGUGGAAGGUGUGAAAACAGAAGGGGGUGUCAGCGGUUUCAUAUCUGGCCUUGGAAAAGGGCUUGUUGGCACUGUAACCAAGCCAGUGGCAGGCGCCCUGGAUUUUGCAUCAGAAACAGCCCAGGCGGUGAGAGACACAGCCACACUCAGCGGCCCCAGGACUCAAGCACAGAGGGUUCGGAAACCGCGUUGCUGCACGGGGCCCCAGGGGCUGCUUCCCCGAUAUUCUGAGAGCCAGGCGGAAGGACAGGAGCAGCUCUUCAAACUCACAGACAACAUACAGGACGAAUUCUUCAUCGCUGUGGAGAACAUUGACAGCUACUGCGUGCUCAUCUCCUCCAAAGCUGUUUACUUCCUGAAAAGUGGAGACUACGUGGAUCGAGAAGCCAUUUUCCUAGAAGUCAAAUACGAUGACCUCUACCACUGCCUUGUCUCCAAAGACCAUGGGAAGGUGUAUGUGCAGGUGACCAAGAAAGCCGUGAGCACGAGCAGUGGAGUGUCCAUCCCCGGCCCCUCCCACCAGAAGCCCAUGGUCCAUGUGAAAUCUGAGGUCCUUGCUGUCAAGUUGUCACAAGAAAUAAACUACGCAAAGAGCCUCUACUAUGAACAGCAGCUUAUGUUAAGACUCAGCGAAAACCGAGAGCAGCUGGAGCUGGACUCCUGAAGCCCCGCUGCUGAGAUGGGCGCUCCCGACACAGCGCAGACCCACCAGGAGGAAAGAGGCCCAGCUCUCAGCUGACGAUGGAGGCAGAACCGGAGUCGGGUUUGGGGAAGUUGUCAAGGAAUGAGGGAAAGUAAAUCCUCAUGAGGAAAAGUACAAAUGGAAAUCGUAUUAAUUUGUGAGGCAGGGAGUUAUUUUAGAUUAUGGGAAAUAAUUUUUAAAGGUAUUGGUUAAAUAACGUUUAAAAACAUGUACUGAGAUGAAUCUAAUUUUUAGAUUGCCCUGUAUUUUGUUAACAUGUAUAUAUGUACAACAGUGUGUUUGUAAAUAUAUAGGAACGUUUCUGAACAGGGUCUGUGCUAUGUGUAAAGGUUUGUUAACUGUAAAGUAAUAUAAAGUUAUAUUGGAUCUUCUAUUGCACUAAUUCUAGAUGUCUAAUUCAGGAUACUGUCUAUAGAAAGGCAUUCUUAAAAGUUAAAGAAUGUUACGUCUUAGUUUUGGAGACUAAAGUAUUCCCAGUAAAGUGGGUUGAGGUGAGGGCUGUGGUCCUGAAAGGGACGCCUUUGACAUCGUGGCUGUCCAGUUGGGCUGUGAGCUGUGGCACCCAGGACUGGCGCUGGCCCUUCAGAAGGAUCUAGGAGAGGGGCUUGGGAGCCCACUUUUAAUUUCUCACCCCCAUUUUACAAAGAGUGCUUAGAUUCUUACAAAUUAUGAUGUAAGUUAUCCAUUUGGCUUUUUCCUAACUAGUCUUACCAAACUUAGGGGGAAACCUGUGCUCCAUUACCACAUGGGUGCAAGUCAGCAUUGUAAGUUUUCUCAGGUUAUUAUUAUUAGAGAGGUUGGAAACAUUGGUAAACUCUGUUGAUUGAGAAGGAAAAAAAAAGUCCCAUUGAACUGUUGCAACAAAUCAGAAAUCCACAUAAAAGUGCUCUCCUGCCUGGGCAGCAACAACCAAGAACAAAGCCCCGGGACUGUUUUCUUUUUAAUAAAGCCACAGGCAGGCAUCGUAGCUCCACAGCCCGAGGGGACACAGGAUGGAAACCCCAGGAUGAGAAGGGAGCAGGGAGAGUUCCAGAAAGGGGGAUGAAAUAGGAGUAUUAAAAAGCUGCGUUGGUAAGUUUUUCAUGGAACCAAGAUUUGACAAAGGCAUCUCUUAUCCUUGGUUUUAAAUUCCUGCUGGGAGCAAGGCCUGGUAUGAGCGCCCUGGGUCUUGUUUUUGGUGUUUCGCUUUUCUGUAAGGAUUAAGCAGAUAGGGAGAAGGGAAAAGGGGCCUCACUUUAGAAUGAAUGAGUCACCUUGUGAUUUUUAAAUUUUUAUUUUAAUAAAGCUAAUCAAUUUCUACAACCUUGUCACAUGUAGCUGAGUCUGGGAUGACUCAGUGGAUCAGUGGAUGCGUGGAAGGUUUUGGUGUUUAUAACUCAUGACCCAAAUCCUUCCAAGACACAAAUGAAGCUAAUCUUCUUCCCCUCCCUUUCCUCUCCCACUUCCCCUCUGUGUCUGUGUCUGUGUGUGUGUGUGUGUGUGUGUGUGUGUGCGCGCGCGCGCGUGCAUGCAGAGAGGAAGGAAGGGAGCUUUAGCACAAGUAGCUACAUAGUGUUCAAGGAUCAGCUUUCUUGAACUCCGAGGCUUGGUUGCCUUUGCUGAACUCCAAGUUAGUGGAUUGCAGAAUGGAAACUUGGCUUUUGCGGCACUGGGUGAGUUUUAGUUUGUGUGUGUCUUGCUGGGGGGUGGUGAUGAUUGUCUCAGCACUCACGCACUGCACAAGAUGGCAGCAGGAUACAGCACUGCACAAGAUGGCAGCUCCUCUGCAGCUUCCUCCUCAGCCUCCCUCCUUGCACCCCCACAGGUUUGGCUUGUGGUUUUUGUCAUCAGUAACCUACUGCCUGAGAUCAUGAUCUCUUAAAAGAUGAGACUCUCGGAAGGGUUGAUUGUAUGCGUCAGUGAGCCUUCUAUCACCUUCUGGAACAAAGUCACUUGAAAUCUCUUGAUGAGAUUAAGGAGUUUAGUGUUACUAAGAAAAUCUGCUUUGGGCCGCAGCAGUGCUGGGUGUUCUCAGACCUGACUGAGGAAGUUAGCUGCGGGCUGCCCUGUGGGCUGGUGCUUCAGGAGGAAUCCAGAGAAGUGUUCAGAUGCCCCCCUUGGGCUCCUUUCUAAUUUUAAUCAGCUCUUUAAAUAGCUGCCCAUCUCCUGUGAUUGCACAACCAAGCACUUUGACAUUUGCACCUUAGGAGAGGCAGAUGUUAAAAUGGAAUCCAAAGACCACCUAGGGCGGGGCUGGGUGGGAGAUGGGAGGGCCAACUGCGAGCUGCUCCACUUCUCAGCUCUCCCCUGCCCUGCAGCCCUGGGCCAGACAAGGCCAGAAGGUUUCAGGGGCAUUUGACAUCCCCUCCUGGUUCUCACCAGGAAAACAUCCAAAGCUUUGGAGGAAACAGGCCCUGCCCCUGGCUCCUUAAAUGCCCCGUCUCUUUGUAAACUGAUAUUCAGCCAGCAAUGCCUAAGACUUUGUUAAGAUCAUUUCUACUGCUUUUCUUUCUGCUUCAAACACACAGUUCGUCUCUGAGGAAAGUAAAAUAAAUGGAAUAAGAGUAAAUUGGGUAAGGAGAUAUCCAAAGCUACCCAGUCCCUUGACCCAGCACAGUUGGCCGACCCGUGUCACUCCCUGGCUGUCGCUGCUUCUCUGUGCUCACUGAAGGGUGAGCCAGGCCAGUGCUUCCCCAGCCCCUGGGCCUGGUCACUACACAGUGGAAAACAGACAAGCGGCCCCUUCCCCAAAUCCCAAGAGUGUCUUGCUGCUUGGUGGGUGCUCAUCGCAAUGUUCUGAAGGCUCCAGGGCCACUUUGUUUGUAAGUAUGAUCUGGGCCUCAAAAUACCAUAGUAGCUGCUUGAUAAAAUUCUAAAAAUAUCUGGUUCUCUAUUAUGUAAACACUAUUACAGUCACCAGUGUGUGAAGACUCUUGAGUCUGGUUCUCAUAUCAGAGUCAUCAUUUUUCUUCCUGUGGAAUAAAAUGCCUUGUGGACUUCCCAAA